GGAAGUGCAUCGGCCCCGGGUCUGUCCGGGCGUUGCGGGAUUGGGGCCUGGGAACGCUCGGCCCCCGGCAGCCGAGAAGCCCGUGACUGGGCUGAGCAGCACCAUCCCAGCCCUGGGGCCUGCUGACUGCCCAGUCCCGGCUUCACCUGCAGCGAACCCGGAGCGUUGCUAUCCUCCACCGGACUGUCAGGCUCUGCGCGCCCCGCGGAGGUCGGCGGCGACCAGCAGCGACUGCGGAGCGACGGCGGGCGGCCCCGGGCAUGUACGCCCCCGGAGGCGCAGGGCUGCCCGGCGGGCGCCGGCGGAGGAGCCCGGGAGGCAGCGCUCUGCCCAAGCAGCCGGAGCGUAGCCUGGCCUCGGCCCUGCCUGGCGCCCUGUCUAUCACGGCGCUGUGCACUGCCCUCGCCGAGCCCGCCUGGUUGCACAUCCACGGAGGCACCUGUUCGCGCCAGGAGCUGGGGGUCUCCGACGUGUUGGGCUAUGUGCACCCGGACCUGCUGAAAGAUUUCUGCAUGAAUCCCCAGACAGUGCUGCUCCUGCGGGUCAUCGCCGCCUUCUGUUUCCUGGGCAUCCUGUGUAGUCUCUCCGCUUUCCUUCUGGAUGUCUUUGGGCCGAAGCAUCCUGCUCUGAAGAUCACUCGUCGCUAUGCCUUCGCCCAUAUCCUAACGGUUCUGCAGUGUGCCACCGUCAUUGGCUUUUCUUAUUGGGCUUCUGAACUCAUCUUGGCCCAGCAGCAGCAGCAUAAGAAGUACCAUGGAUCCCAGGUCUAUGUCACCUUCGCCGUUAGCUUCUACCUGGUGGCAGGAGCUGGUGGAGCCUCAAUCCUGGCCACGGCAGCCAACCUCCUGCGCCACUACCCCACAGAGGAAGAGGAGCAGGCGCUGGAGCUGCUCUCAGAGAUGGAAGAGAACGAGCCCUACCCGGCGGAAUAUGAGGUCAUCAACCAGUUCCAGCCACCCCCUGCUUACACACCCUAAUGCCAGCCCUGGGCUCUCUUCCUCGGCAGCCCCUCCCUCAACUCUGCAGCUCCUCUCGCACCCAGAGGAGCUCCUUUCCCCAGCAGGCCUCACUGGUAGGAUCCUGACCAUCUUCUCCAAACCUUCCCCAGGAGAGACUCUGCCUUUAGGGUCAUCCAAGUAUCCCUGCUCUCAGAACCGGAGGUCCACUGGUUUUCUAUAAUGUACUCUUUCCCUCCUGCCACAUCCUGCCCCCUUCACAUUCACGAGUCAUUACCAGCCAGGGAAGGUCAUCCAAGUUUCCUCCAGCAUGGGCGAUAUCUUUGGGACCGAGACUUUCCUUGGAGAGCUGCUGAGAGCGGACAGUCCCAAAAACAAGUGUCAAAGGGCCCAAGGGAAAGGGGACUGUGCCCUGGAGGCUCACUUCACAGGGAUCAGUGUUUGCUCCACAGCUGUAGCUCUGGGCUGACGCCCCCCAGACCCCUUCCUUCUCGGAGUGACCCGCCCCCAGGCCACCUGCUCCGGGGAGUUCUGUGCACUUUACUCUUUGGACUUCUCCUCACGUGUGCCCUGGUUUUAUGGGGAGAGGGAAUCGCUGUUGGGAAGGCAGAGCAGUUGCAACCCUCUCUGCCCUUGCUUCAUGUGGCUGGAGCCCAGGCAAGGAGAGCAGGAGCCAGCGUGAGACUGAGGCCCCCUGGUGCCUAUCAAGGACCAGAGUGAAGGGGACUACAUCUCCCAGCCCUUCACCUUUUAAAUAUGAGUGGUUUUAAAAGGAAAAAAAUGAAACCAGGCAACAGCAACAAUAUUCUGUUUUUAAAAUAGGGACAAGACUGUUGUCACUUUUUAGACAUGUAUCCCAUUCCUUUUGGCUCUGCAAUAUUUGGGGCUGUAGCUCCUUCCAAGCCCAUGGUAGUCCCUCCCCGAGUCUCUCCCAGUAGAAUGCAGCCUCCCUUCCCUGGCCCCUUCCCUCUCAGUGACGGUGACUCCCUGGGGCCUUCUCGUGGAACCCAGAGGGGCUGAGGACUGUGGCCUGGCUGGCGGGCCAGCGUGGUGCUCCUCAGGACUGCAGCACUGAGAUGGAACCUGGCCUCAGUUUAGGAACAGGGGCCACAACAGGGCAGGAACCCACCACCCUCCACAUAGGAAUACAACCAGUGGGGCCACAUCAUGUGAGGCAUCAGACCCACACUGUCAGCCCAGCAGGCCGGGCUGUGUCCUUCAGACCCAGUGCUGCCCUAGACUCUGACUCGGGACUCCAGCUUGCCACGUGCCCUCUCCCCUCUUGAAUGUACUCUGGUCUUGCAGUGUGCUGCUGGGACUUUCUUGCUCAGCCAUCACUCUGGUCACCUUGUUUGCUCUGGGUCUGGCUGAAUUUUCUGCCCUGAGAUCUGGGCAUAAAGUGGAUGAAACUUGAAAGACCUUCAGUGUAGAUCCAGAUGGCCAACCUGUCCUUGUUAAGUUACUUGCUUCUUGGGAAUCAGUGUCCCCUGCUGAGCUGAAAAGGAAAUGGAUUCCAAUCUCUUCCAACCUUUAAGGUGAUAGAUAGUUUGAGCAAGACUGGAGAAUGGACAACACUAUGAAGCUGUGGCUAGAAAGGGACUGUCAUGUCCCAUCCUUUGGCCAGAUUGACUGGGGAUGUCCGGACAGAUGCCUGCAUGGGUGGUGAGGGCCACAUCUGCACACGAGCCAGUGGCUGCUUGCAGUUCACUGCUGUGAUGCCAGAGUGUGUUCAAAGGUGACUCUCCUGCUCUUCUGGACUCUUCUCUCAGGCAAGAAAGGCUGCAGGCUGCCUGCUAUGUGAUGCCUGAGCACAAAGCCAAGGAACUGAACUAAGUCUUUCUGUUAAGUCCUGAGUUUGUCAUUGGCAGGUUUACUUGUGGCCAGCUCUCUCUGCCCUUGGGUGUCUGAGCAGGCAGACCAGAAGACCAGGCACUGGACCUGCAUGCCAAAGGGACUGGUCAUCUCCUGAGGACCUGUAAAUGACCCUGUGGACUGUUCCGCACGAUCCGGAACCCACUUUUUAUUCACUCCCCAUGUCUUUGGCCUUCCUCUUCUUUCUCUUUCCCUCUGCCAUCCUGACACUGAUAGUUUGUCAUAUAAAUUCCCCGGGUUGUGUUUUUUUUUCUAGAAAAAAAUUAAAAGGGAAAACAAAACCAAAAAAACCAGAAACCACGAAUAAGAAUGGAAAUGACAAUGGCUGCCUGUCAUUUUUCUGUCACGAUUUUCCUGAUUUGGUUUGUUCCCUUUGUCUCAGAGAAGCAGGAGAUGUUGAUGAGGCUGUAUUUUUUUUUCUUUUUCUUGUUUUUGAGACAAGAGUCUCGCUCUGUCACCCGGGCUGGAGUGUAACGUGGCAUGAUCUCAGCUCACUGCAACCUCUGCCUCCUGGGUUCAAGCGAUUAUCCUGCCUCAGCCUCCUGAGUAGCUGGGAUUACAGGCAUGCGCCACUAUGCCCAGAUAAUUUUUUUGUAUUUUUAGUAGAGACAGGGUUUCACCAUGUUGGCCAGGCUGGUCUGGAACUCCUAACCUCAGGUUAUCCACCCACCUUGGCCUCCCAAAGUGCUGGGAUUAUAGGCAUGAACCACCGUGCCUGGCCAAAGAUGUAAUUUAAAAUAGUUAGAAGGGACUUGGCAUGGGCCAGCUCCGUGCAUGGCAUUUUCACCCCCAGAGCUUCCUAAUCCUGUUUUCACACAGGAAGUUUCUAGGUCUUUCUAGAACAGCUAGAAAUAGUAGCUGACUCCCGCCCAAGGCCCAACCUUCAAACCCUGAGCUCUUCAGGCUGCAUCCUCUGGUGAGCUAUAGAGGAGAACGUGGCUCCUAAACUCUAGCCAUCCUGUGGGAGGAAAUAGACUUCUUUGGGCUGUGGCUUGCAGAACAAACUACACUUUUUUUCCCUCUAUUGUUUAAAUUUUAUUUAAUAAUUUGUGUGUUUUUCUGUCUUUAUUUUCUGUAUUUCACGUGUUCCUUCACUCCCUAGAAACUGCACUUUCUUUGAAACCAUAGGUAAUGAAUCUUACUAGGAGAGGCAUGGGGAUAGAGACAGUUCUGGGAGUGUGACCUGUAAGCCUCCUGUAGGGCAGUGCCAGGCCUUGAUUGCCCACGUUCUCUCCGUUCCUUCUUCCUUCAUACAUUUGAUCACACAGCCUACACCCAGCCCCGAGUGUGCAUCACGGUAAAAGAGCUGAGGGCUCUCUUCAGGGAGCAGCCCAUUUAGGUCUCUUUUGUUGUUGUUAGGGAGAAUACACAUCUUUCUUGGAAGCUGGGAGUGUGUUCUCAUUUCAUGUCCAUUCAGACAAAGCACCAUUAGGCACCAUGAAAUAUACAGUGACGGACAGGACCCUGUCUGCAAGGAUUUUAUGUCCUUAGUUCAGGAGAUGGACUUGUCCACAGAAAGGCAGAGUGAAGUGGGCGGCCGGCUCGGAAAAGUCCUGUGCCCAGAAGGGAGCCAGUUCUGACCUGAGUGAUAAUGAAAGGCUUCCUGGAGGACGCAGCUUGAGCCACACUUGAUGUGGGAGUGAACUGGGAUAGGGACACUCCUGCUGAGAGAAUGGCAAGAGCAAAAGCACACUGGUGGCCAGGAGGUGGUAAGAGCCGAGGUUAGAAAGGUGAGGGGUGCUCAUUUAAGGCACUAACAGCAGAAGGAGCCCAGGAAGGAUUUUCAGAAGGGAAGGGAGGGAUGCAACCUUAUUUUAAUGACUGGUGACAGUAGGAAGGGUUCUGCCUGGCCUUAAGUGAGGGUGUUGAAAGUGGGAGACAGGACCUGCCAAAGGGGAAGAGGGCGGUCACAGUCAAUCCCAGGGCCCAGUGUCUCAGCCAGGUGCUGGAGUUGGGAAUGCGGGAGCCCCAGUCUCUGCCCACCUGUCACGUGGCAGCUGGAAGGUGGCAUCAACUGCACAGGCGAAGAGGGGCCCGCACACGAGAAGCCAUGGGAUGUGAAGGGCCGCAAGGAGAGGACCCUGGGACACAGGAAGAGGUGGUGCAUCUGGGGCAGGGCGGCUUUCCCAAGAUGACUAGAGAAUCUUCAGCUGGCAUCUUGCCUGAAAUAUCCACGCUCUCAGCCACUACACUAAUGGAACACAGAUGCUAUGGGGAGACAGAAGGGAACUGACAAACUUCAUGCCCCUGUUUUCAAAUAGCCUGCAAUCUUACCUCUUCCUCUGCAUUUUUUGGGGGGAGUGACAUUUUAAUGGGAGGCAGGAGGUUUGUGGAGAAGAGAAAAUGUUUUUUUUGUGGGGGUGGGUAGAGACAGUCUCACCAUGUUGCCCAGGCUGGUCUCAAACUACUGGCUUCAGGCAAUCCUUCUGCCUCCCUUCCCAAAGGGUUGGGAUUACAGGCUUGAGCCACUGCACCAAGCCUGAAAAUGUCGUUUUGAAUGAGCCCACCUGAAACGAAGACGCUUCAUUAGGGUUACUGGUUUGAGAAUUAAGAUCAGUUCUGGCCGGGUGCGGUGGCUCACGCCUAUUAUCCCAGCACUUUGGGAGGCCGAGGUGGGUGGAUCACAAGGUCAGGAGAUCGAGACCAUUCUGGCCAACAUGGUGAAACCCCGUCUCUACUAAAAAUACAAAAAUUAACCAGGCAUGGUGGCAGGUGCCUGUAGUCCCAGCUACUCGGGAGGCUGAGGCAGGAGAAUCACUUGAACCCGGGAGGCAGAGGUUGCAGUGAGCCGAGAUCAUGCCACUGGACUCCAGCCUGACAGAGUGAGACUCCAUCUCAAACACACACACACACACACACACACACCACACACACACACACAGGUUCCUCACCAUAAGCUUUGGGGAAAAUUCUUGGCUUUUUUGCUGGGGGAGAGAGCAGUGCCCAGGGAAGAUUGGCUGAUCUCAGAGCUGGAGGGUUUAUGCGGGACUGGCCAGCCCCUUCAGCUGAGUGGGACAGCAACACAGUGGGUGGUAAGGGGCUUCAUAAGAUGUACAAGAUGAGGGAGAGGCCCCUCCAGCCAACCCUGUGUCUAAAGAGUCAGGUAACGAAGAACUUUCCAGAGACAGCUGUGAGUCCGUCUGGCUUAAGGGGUUGUACAGGUGUCUGAGAAUGGGGCCUGAAGGUGCAGGGCCUGCAGGCUGCCCUGUUUGGAAGGUUCCUGUCCUUCUGUCUUGGUAGAAAAUGGCAGCUAGCCUUGUAAAGGGCCUCCUUGUGUAGCGAGAUAGACCAUGUAGCCCCAGAUGCCCCCAUGGCUUCACUUCCCUCUUGGGGGUCUCUCAGUAUAUGUCUAGUGCCACCACUAUUGGUGGAGAGUUUCCUUCUGGAAUAACCUUGGGGUGGUGGAUGGGUUUUAUUUUAAUAAAAGAAGAAUGUCUCAUUCA